ACUGGAGCGUCUCCUGCUCGCGCACGCCAGAAGCAGCUCGGGGUCUCUCCGCCGCCCCUUGGCCAUGGCCGCUGUGCCGACGGCGCCCGCUCCCCUGCGCUCCAGGGGCCCCCGCCGCUGCAGCCGCAGCCGCCGCAGCUUCUGAGCCCAAGGGGCCGCCGCUGCAGCCGCCGCCGCCGCCGCUCGCCCGCCCGGAUCCCGCCUGCGGCAGUUGCCGCACAACAUGCUACCUGCGGCCGCCCCGGCGGCUCCUGGAACCCCGGUUCGCGGCGAUGCCAGCCACCCCAGCGAAGCCGCCGCAGUUCAGUGCUUGGAUAAUUUGAAAGUACAAUAGUUGGUUUCCCUGUCCACCCGCCCCACUUCGCUUGCCAUCACAGCACGCCUAUCGGAUGUGAGAGGAGAAGUCCCGCUGCUCGGGCACUGUCUAUAUACGCCUAACACCUACAUAUAUUUUAAAAACAUUAAAUAUAAUUAACAAUCAAAAGAAAGAGGAGAAAGGAAGGGAAGCAUUACUGGGUUACUAUGCACUUGCGACUGAUUUCUUGGCUUUUUAUCAUUUUGAACUUUAUGGAAUACAUCGGCAGCCAAAACGCCUCCCGGGGAAGGCGCCAGCGAAGAAUGCAUCCUAACGUUAGUCAAGGCUGCCAAGGAGGCUGUGCAACAUGCUCAGAUUACAAUGGAUGUUUGUCAUGUAAGCCCAGACUAUUUUUUGCUCUGGAAAGAAUUGGCAUGAAGCAGAUUGGAGUAUGUCUCUCUUCAUGUCCAAGUGGAUAUUAUGGAACUCGAUAUCCAGAUAUAAAUAAGUGUACAAAAUGCAAAGCUGACUGUGAUACCUGUUUCAACAAAAAUUUCUGCACAAAAUGUAAAAGUGGAUUUUACUUACACCUUGGAAAGUGCCUUGACAAUUGCCCAGAAGGGUUGGAAGCCAACAACCAUACUAUGGAGUGUGUCAGUAUUGUGCACUGUGAGGUCAGUGAAUGGAAUCCUUGGAGUCCAUGCACGAAGAAGGGAAAAACAUGUGGCUUCAAAAGAGGGACUGAAACACGGGUCCGAGAAAUAAUACAGCAUCCUUCAGCAAAGGGUAACCUGUGUCCCCCAACAAAUGAGACAAGAAAGUGUACAGUGCAAAGGAAGAAGUGUCAGAAGGGAGAACGAGGAAAAAAAGGAAGGGAGAGGAAAAGAAAAAAACCUAAUAAAGGAGAAAGUAAAGAAGCAAUACCUGACAGCAAAAGUCUGGAAUCCAGCAAAGAAAUCCCAGAGCAACGAGAAAACAAACAGCAGCAGAAGAAGCGAAAAGUCCAAGAUAAACAGAAAUCGGUAUCAGUCAGCACUGUACACUAGAGGGUUCCAUGAGAUUAUUGUAGACUCAUGAUGCUGCUAUCUCAACCAGAUGCCCAGGACAGGUGCUCUAGCCAUUAGGACCACAAAUGGACAUGUCAGUUAUUGCUCUGUCUAAACAACAUUCCCAGUAGUUGCUAUAUUCUUCAUACAAGCAUAGUUAACAACAAAGAGCCAAAAGAUCAAAGAAGGGAUACUUUCAGAUGGUUGUCUUGUGUGCUUCUCUGCAUUUUUAAAAGACAAGACAUUCUUGUACAUAUUAUCAAUAGGCUAUAAGAUGUAACAACGAAAUGAUGACAUCUGGAGAAGAAACAUCUUUUCCUUAUAAAAAUGUGUUUUCAAGCUGUUGUUUUAAGAAGCAAAAGAUAGUUCUGCAAAUUCAAAGAUACAGUAUCCCUUCAAAACAAAUAGGAGUUCAGGGAAGAGAAACAUCCUUCAAAGGACAGUGUUGUUUUGACCGGGAGAUCUAGAGAGUGCUCAGAAUUAGGGCCUGGCAUUUGGAAUCACAGGAUUUAUCAUCACAGAAACAACUGUUUUAAGAUUAGUUCCAUCACUCUCAUCCUGUAUUUUUAUAAGAAACACAAGAGUGCAUACCAGAAUUGAAUAUACCAUAUGGGAUUGGAGAAAGACAAAUGUGGAAGAAAUCAUAGAGCUGGAGACUACUUUUGUGCUUUACAAAACUGUGAAGGAUUGUGGUCACCUGGAACAGGUCUCCAAUCUAUGUUAGCACUAUGUGGCUCAGCCUCUGUUACCCCUUGGAUUAUAUAUCAACCUGUAAACAUGUGCCUGUAACUUACUUCCAAAAACAAAAUCAUACUUAUUAGAAGAAAAUUCUGAUUUUAUAGAAAAAAAAUAGAGCAAGGAGAAUAUAACAUGUUUGCAAAGUCAUGUGUUUUCUUUCUCAAUGAGGGAAAAACAAUUUUAUUACCUGCUUAAUGGUCCACCUGGAACUAAAAGGGAUACUAUUUUCUAACAAGGUAUAUCUAGUAGGGGAGAAAGCCACCACAAUAAAUAUAUUUGUUAAUAGUUUUUCAAGUUUUGUUCACUCUGUUUUAUUGUUUGUUUUAUUGAGAAAUUCUUACUCUUAGAGACUCAUGAAUUAAGAAAGAGAAUUCUGCUAACUCAGAGAACCUGGUUCCUAUGUAAUUCAGAAUAUAUUACAUUUCUCAGUAAUAUUUGUUUUUUGAAUCCACCUUUAUCUGAGCCAAUGGAGAUUUACUUAUAGCGUAUUAGGAGAUAUUUAUUCCAUUUUCUUAUUUUAAUCAACAUUCUAAUUAUAGACACAUGGGCCUCCCUAGCUGAUUUCACUGCUCCCCCUUCAUUGCUUAGAAAUGGGCAUCAUUUCUUGUAUGUCAGAUCCCCCUGCAUCUUCAACAUUUAGUCUUUUCUUCUCCAUAUUUUCUAUCUGUGGAUCUCUUUAGGGGAUUGAAGUCACCCUAGCUGAAGGCCUCACCAGUGUUUCACAGAGGACACAGCCCACCCCUUGCAGGAGGAGGUAUCUCUGAGUGUGCAGCACAGAAUCGCAUGACCCACCUUAACCUUCCUGUUGUCAUGGAAGGAUGCACGGCUGCUCUGUCCACUGUGAUUCCUAGCCCUCUCAAGAUCACUGCUUUCUGAAGAAUUUGCAAUGACUCUGGCUUCUGGCUGCUUAUCUCUGGACACCCGUUCUCCACCAGUUGUACAGUUCAUGUAAUCUACUUGGCUUAAUUGAUUUUCCACUUCUCUCUUCCUCUUCUAAGAUAUAAACAUUUUAAAUGAUUUAUUCCUGUUUCUUAUUCUGGUGUUUCUUUCCUUGUCCCUAUGAGAUAAGUGUCUCAACUCACUAAAUCUAUUCCCAAUGUAUAAAAUAAUUCUAAUUCCAUUUUCAGCUAAAACAUAUAUUACCAAGAAGAAACAAACUUUAUCCUACAGAAUGAUGUUAGGUAGAAAUAUGUCCCCAGGUUUGAGACCUUUCGGAUGAUUUCAUAUACCAUCUUUCUUCUGAGUGUUACCCAGUCAAGUAUAAGUAGCCAAAUUAUUUUUGCACAUCUUUCUGUUUCUCAUGUCUUCAUUUAUUCAACAAGCACUUACUGGGAAGGUCUACACCUGCAUAGGCAAUGCUGGAAAAAGGGUUAAGUAAACCAGGACAUGACAAUGGUGGCAAAUGACUAUCAGGUCUUCCCAUGUGUUUGACUCAAACUUAUUACCCUAUGGUCCUUCUGACAAUGGCAGAAGGUCUGAAUCCUUGAUGCUAAACUUAUAUAAAAGUAGAAUUAUUACAAAGGAAAAAGAAAUAAAAACUAACAUUCAUUUUCAUAUGUUGGAUGAAAUAUAAAUGAAGAAAAAGAUAACAUCAAUUUUAACUGUAAUUCUCCAUCCACCAGUAACAGAUCCUUAAGACAAUAGAAUCAUACAGUAUUCAAACCAGCAGCCUUCUCAAAUUUGAGCAAAAACUCUAUCAACCUCUGGUAAAGUUCCUACACUAGUCACAGAAGGUGUUAACUUUCUACUCUGAUUCUGUCUCCAUAAUGGGGUAAACUGUUGAUAGUUUACCCCAUCAACAGAUGGUCGGUAAAUUAUUGAUUCGAAGAAUCGAGAGAGUGCAGCAACAUAAAUCUGUUAAUGUCUGAUCAAGCUCCUGCCCUGUUCUCCGAAUUCAGCUUCAUAAUUAAGGGAAGGCCUGUUUUCUAUCCUCAGAUUUAGGUUCUAGUAGCAGUUGUGUAACCACUAGUGAGUCACUUAACUCCUCUGGGUCCCCAUUUCUCAUGUGCAACAAGAAAGAGGGGAACUGGAGAUGAUCACUCUAGUUCCAGACAAGGGAACAUUUCACACUUUGUUUACUUCAGGGUGAUGUCCCUGAGUCCUCAUUAGUGACUGCGUCCUUUGGAAGUUAUCCCAACCCUGCUUUUCUCAAAAGUGAAAAUGUAUAGGCUCUCAGAGGAGACAGAUUUAACUCUGCUUCUCUAAUGUUAUUGAAUUAAAAGCUGUUCACAUUAGUGGUUAUUAAAUAUUGAAAUAACACUGGGAAGAAAAAGCAUAUAUAAAUACAGCUAAAAACAAGAAUAGAUAUUCAUUCUCACAAAGGGAGACAGCAAAGAAAAUGGAAAGUGCACUGGUGCUAGCGUUAGACAGCUUGUGUUAAUGUCUCAAUUCUGCUACUAACUGGUUGCAGCUUGUGUGACCUUGGGCACAUUGUAUGAUCUCGCAGAAUAUCAUCCCAAAUCUGCAAAAUGGAAUUGGCAUCAUCUCUUUUGCAAGAUUGUUAUGAGAAUUAAAAGGUUCUUCAUUCAAUAUAAUAAUAAAUAUUUUGUAUAUAAAUGAAUAUCAAUUAAAAGUUAUGACUAAUUCCACAAGUCAAACAUAUAAAUUUUAUUUCUUGAUUCAUGAUAUGUGAUAGUAUUCAUAAAAAUGUACAUGCAUGAUAAUUUCAAGGAAUAAGUAUAUAUGUGAGAAUCAUGGAAAUGAAAUUAAUAAUAUUAACUAGUAAUUAAAUUGUAA